AGAGGAGCCGGGACACCGAGGGAAGAGGCCGGAGGGAGAUCGCGGAGGGGAGGGGGCGGGAGGGGGGUGGGGUAUCCUGAGUCGUCCGUGGUCCGGAGUCUGGAAGGCCCUAGAGCGGCGCCAGUCGACCCGCCUCGCCACAACUUGCCCAGACCAGACACGUUUCAUCCUGCGCCCUGCAAGAAGGAGCCGGCCUGCCUCUCUCCGCUUUGCUGCUCCUCGGCCUCCGCGGGCCCGGCCCGCGUCAGCAGCGACCCUGGGGUCUGGGUCCCCUGUGUCGCCCCCGCCCGCCUGCAGCGCCCGGCACCCGCCCAGGAGCGCGCAGCUGGGGUGAGCCGAGACCGGGGAUGCGCCAGGCGCCCACAGGAGGUGGCUGACGGGGCAUCCCGAUACCCGCGAAGCCGGCCCUCCUGCCUCUCCAGGCUGCGAGCCGAGCCUCUGCAGAUCCAGCUGGAGUAGCCGCCGCUGCCCCCACUGCCUGUUUGCCUUCCAAGGAAGGGCGCCGAGGUUCCCCUGGAACCCGCGUCUCUCGGCUUUUGUCUGCUGGUUCGGCUGCCCGGCGGUGCCAUGCGCCUGGGACUUGAGGCGCCGCGCAAGGCUGGGGGCCCUGCCCGGGAUGGGGGAGGGAGGGAACGGGAAAGCAUGCCCCCUUCUUUCCUGUUCCGGCCAUCUUGUGACCGAGAUCCACGCAAGGGGAAAGGGGUGGUCAGCGGCACGACGCCCCACGAUGGAGUGUGGCGGCCAACGGAGAUGGGUACCUCGGGCCCGCAGGCCUCUGCGCCCAGAUCUCAGCGGGGGCGCGCGGGCCACCCCCACGUUCAGCUCUGAAGCCCUUGGCCCAGAUCAUGGGUUAAUCGUUCUAACAGGCCAGAGGCAGCAAAAAUAGGAGGGAUAAAGGGCCAGGAGCUGAUGUUUCCUUAACUAAGCGCCUAAGUCAUUCGAUCGUUCUUCAUUCACGUGUCCAUUCAGCAAAUUCUGAACGCCUUCUCCGUGCCUGUCCUCUGCUAGGUUCUAGGGACGUAUACUUGAGCAAGAGAGACCACAGCUCUUGUUCCCGCUGAUCCUGCAGCCCAGUGGAUGGAGUCCAGAAUCUACAGACCUGCCAGGAAAGAAAAAAAAAUUCCUGAUGUCUGGUCCAAGCAGGAAUUCCCCGGUGGAUUGGGGAAUGUCUGGCUUUUCCUCAGCUUAUUGAUCUCUGUGGUAACCACUGGAGGCCCCCAGAAGACCCAUAGAAAUGAGAGGCCUGAGGUCUACAAGUCGCUGCUAGAAAUAUUUUAGCCUCUCCAAAGCCCAGAAUGCAGCCCCGACCCAAGUUUGUAAGGGUUCUGGGUGCACGCUGACCCUGCGCGGGCAGACGCGCCCUUUGCUCCAGGUCCGGACCUGGGCGCUGCUAUAGCAACGUCCUGGACGCCCAGACCUUAGGCCGCCGCCGCCGCGGAAGCGAGGAACCCGGCCUUCUCCCGCUCCUGAGGGCUGUGGCGGCGGCGGCCCGGGAGGCGGCCCAGGCUGGGUAAAGACCGCCCGGCUCCUCCUAUGCAAGCUGAGGCAGCGGAUUGGUUUUCAAGCAUGCCCUUCCAGAAGCAUGUCUACUACCCGCUCGCCAGCGGCCCAGAGGGGCCCGACGUCGCUGUGGCCGCCGCCGCCGCGGGUGCGGCCUCCAUGGCCUGUGCGCCCCCCAGCGCGGCUUCGGGGCCCCUGCCCUUCUUCCAGUUCAGGCCGCGGCUGGAGAGUGUGGACUGGCGGCGGCUGAGCGCCAUCGACGUGGACAAGGUGGCGGGGGCUGUGGACGUGCUGACGCUGCAGGAGAACAUCAUGAACAUCACCUUCUGCAAGCUGGAAGACGAGAAGUGCCCACACUGCCAGUCGGGGGUGGACCCGGUGCUGCUGAAGCUCAUCCGUCUGGCGCAGUUCACCAUCGAGUACUUGCUGCACUCACAAGAGUUCCUCACCUCGCAGCUGCACACCCUGGAGGAGCGGCUGCGCCUGAGCCACUGCGACGGCGAGCAGAGCAAGAAGCUGCUCACCAAGCAGGCGGGGGAGAUCAAGACGCUCAAGGAAGAGUGCAAACGCCGGAAGAAGAUGAUCUCCACCCAGCAGCUGAUGAUCGAGGCCAAAGCCAACUAUUACCAGUGCCAUUUUUGUGACAAGGCCUUUAUGAACCAAGCUUUUCUACAAAGUCACAUUCAACGCCGCCACACUGAAGAAAAUUCUCAUUUUGAGUAUCAGAAAAAUGCACAGAUUGAGAAGCUCCGGAGUGAGAUCGUCGUAUUGAAGGAAGAGCUGCAGCUCACCAGGUCUGAGCUAGAGGCUGCACACCAUGCCAGUGCAGUCAGAUUCUCCAAGGAAUAUGAAAUGCAGAAAACAAAAGAGGAAGACUUUUUGAAGUUAUUUGACAGGUGGAAAGAAGAAGAAAAGGAGAAACUAGUUGAUGAAAUGGAAAAAGUCAAGGAGAUGUUUAUGAAGGAAUUUAAAGAAUUAACUUCGAAGAAUUCAGCAUUAGAAUAUCAACUGUCAGAAAUCCAGAAGUCCAAUAUGCAGAUCAAGUCCAACAUAGGCACAUUAAAAGAUGCACACGAGUUUAAAGAAGACCGUUCUCCAUAUCCCCAGGAUUUCCAUAAUGUCAUGCAGCUUCUUGAUAGUCAGGAAAGCAAAUGGACAGCUCGAGUUCAAGCUAUUCAUCAAGAACACAAGAAAGAGAAGGGUCGGCUCCUGUCACAUAUAGAGAAACUUCGAACCUCAAUGAUAGAUGAUCUAAAUGCAAGCAAUGUUUUCUAUAAGAAAAGGAUAGAAGAGCUAGGGCAGAGACUCCAGGAGCAGAAUGAGCUGAUUAUAACUCAGAGACAGCAGAUUAAAGACUUUACCUGUAAUCCAUUAAACAGUAUCAGUGAACCCAAAGGAAAUCCUUUAGCCUGGCAGGCUUUUGAAUCUCAGCCAGCUGCUCCAGCUGUGCCUAUGAAUGCCCCAGCCCUGCACACUUUGGAAACUAAAUCAAGUCUGCCAAUGGUGCAUGAACAGGCAUUCUCGUCGCACAUACUGGAACCAAUAGAAGAACUUUCAGAGGAAGAAAAAGGAAGGGAAAAUGAACAGAAAUUAAAUAACAACAAAAUGCAUUUAAGGAAAGCUUUGAAGAGUAACUCCUCCCUCACUAAGGGACUAAGAACAAUGGUGGAGCAGAACUUGAUGGAGAAACUGGAAACCUUGGGGAUUAAUGCAGAUAUACGUGGCAUUUCAAGUGAUCAGUUGCAUAGAGUACUAAAAAGUGUGGAAUCAGAAAGACAUAAGCAAGAAAGAGAAAUACCUAACUUUCAUCAAAUUCGAGAAUUCCUUGAACAUCAAGUCAGCUGUAAAAUUGAGGAGAAAGCACUACUCUCUUCAGAUCAGUGCAGUGUUUCUCAAAUGGAUACCCUUUCAACUGGAGAAGUACCCAAAAUGAUACAACUUCCUUCCAAAAACAGACAACUGAUUAGACAAAAAGCUGUUUCUACUGAUAGGACAUCUGUUCCAAAAAUUAAGAAAAAUGUCAUGGAAGAUCCUUUUCCCAGAAAGUCUUCAACUAUUACGACCCCUCCUUUUAGUUCAGAGGAGGAGCAGGAGGACGACGACCUCAUCCGGGCAUACGCAUCCCCAGGCCCACUUCCUGUGCCGCCACCACAAAACAAGGGCAGCUUCGGGAAGAACACAGUGAAAAGUGACGCGGACGGGACCGAGGGAAGCGAAAUCGAGGACACUGAUGAUUCUCCCAAGCCCGCAGGAGUCGCCGUUAAAACACCUACUGAAAAAGUUGAAAAGAUGUUUCCACAUCGCAAAAAUGUGAACAAACCAGUCGGUGGAACUAAUGUCCCUGAGAUGUUUAUCAAAAAAGAAGAAUUACAAGAACUAAAGUGUGCGGAUGUGGAGGAUGAAGACUGGGACAUAUCAUCCCUAGAGGAAGAGAUAUCUUUGGGAAAAAAAUCUGGGAAAGAACAGAAGGAACCUCCACCUGCGAAAAAUGAACCACAUUUUGCUCAUGUGCUAAAUGCCUGGGGCGCAUUUAAUCCUAAGGGGCCAAAGGGAGAAGGACUUCAAGAAAAUGAAUCAAGCACAUUAAAAAGCAGCUUAGUAACUGUGACUGAUUGGAGCGACACUUCAGAUGUCUAAUUCCACAUGUCAGAAGAUUAUUCCAGAAGCCAGCAGUAUUUCAGUAUCACAGUGUUUCAGUAAUUUGCCUCCAUGAUUCUAGUGCUUCUGCCUUACCGUGUUUCCCACAGCAACACAGAGACUGAUUCAAAGAACAAUGGUCUCUUUAAUGGCACCCAAUACAGUAUUGAAAAUCAGAUCAUCAACAGUAUUUCGAAGCAUGUAAAGGUGUUUAAGACUUCCGCUGCUGCUUAAAAAUAACAUGUCAUUGAAGUCAUAAAAAGUUUUUUCUUCAGAAAGGUACUCUAGUGUUAAGUGUAUUUUUUUCAACUAAUUUUUUAGUGAAUUUUUUUUAAACUUACAGCAUGUUUUGGUUUGAAUUACUAAAACUUUAAAAAAUAUUUUUCUUAUGUAUGCUGUCGUAUCGUAGGCGUUUAUAUUAUAAAAUUCUGUUAGUAGUCUUAAAAUUGAAUUGGUGGAACCACUAAUCCUUAAAAGUUAGUCUGGUUAUUUUUCAUAUAGAAGUAAGUUUAAUCCGAGUGUGGUGGUGUUCACCUUUAAUCCCAGCUACUUGGGAGGCUGAGGUGGGAGGAUAACUUGAGCACAGGAGUUCAAGACCAGCGUGGGCAAUAUAGCAAGACUCCACCCCUCCACACCCCAAAAAAGUAAGUUUAGGAUUAGAAUAUAGCUAGGUCCAAUGUUAAAUACAUUUUCCUGGAGUACAUUUGUCACAUUCAGCUUUGAGCCACUGUAAGCAUGUUACUAUUAAAUGGUUGGUUAUUUUAUAUAGCAUAUUCUUUAUCUUGGAUAUUUUAUGAAUAAAGUAUAGUUAUUUUAAGUGCCAAUUAAUUUAUCAGACUAAAUAGAAAAUAUUUGAGCCAUUACUGAAUUCACAUAUGUAUGUUUUUUUUUACUAUUUAAAAUACCCAACAUGUAUUAUGAAAUACCUCAAAAGUAAUUUAGUUACAUUCUUAAACAAUGACAUUGUCGAAAGAAAGUUCUUAUAAGCUGUUUUUUGCAUUUUUAUAACUUGGUUAUACUAUAUUCUGUUUCCAAGUAACCUUUUAACUAAAAGAUUUGUUGGGUUUUAGAUCUCUUUUCAUUUGUCAACCUUUUCAGUAAAGCCCUCUGUUACAUCACUGUGACUGUGGCUGUGUUAUUAGAGAUGAAUUCUGAGUUAAAUUUGUACUUAUUAGGGGUCUUACAGAGGGAGAAUCUGGCCUUGAUUGCUAUGCCAUAUGACAUUCUGUCCUAAUGGUUAGAACAAAUCUUUAUCUGUUUCCACCCACCCUGGGAUCCUUUUUACUUGUAGCCCAUUCCUGCCCUCUAAAAGAAUCCUUCCAACUUCCUAUAGGGGCCAUUUCAUGCAGAUAUACUCACUUUAUAUGUAUGUUUCUAAAAGCUUUAGUGAAGGCUGAAUCCAAGUUUCAUGUAGUAGGACAGAGAACAGAAGGCCGAAUCCAAGUUUCAUGUGGUAGGACAGAGAACGGCAAUCUACAAAACUACACCAAGCCUAAGAUGGCCCAUGUGCCACUUUGUUCAUUCAUUUAUUUAUUCAGCAGAUAUUUAUUGAACCACUUGGUCUGGUUUGGUUUUGAACACGCACUAAUUCAUUUAAUUACAACAACUUUGCGAUGUAGUUAUUGUUAUAAUCCUCAUCCUAAAGGUGUGAGAAACAGAGUUAUUAAGUAAGUUGCCAGAAGCCAUACAAGUACAAAGUGUCAAGGGGAGACUUUAAGCCAGGUCUCUAUUCCAUGUUUUGUGUCUGCCAUGUUUUCAUUCCUGAGCAGAAGAGCUUGGGGAAAUGAACUUUUGCUAAGUAAACCCAGUAUUUAAAUUAAGUCACUAUAUCUGUGUCUUUUAAGAGCCCCUCCUUUAGCUUACAUGGUUAGUUGUAUCUUUUUUUUUUUUUUUUUUUGAGACAGAGUCUCACUAUGUUGCCCAGGCUUGAGCGCAGUGGCACCAUCUCGGCUCACUACAACCUCCGCCUCCCAGAUUCAAGCGAUUUUCCUGCCUCAGCCUCCCAAGUAGCUGGGAUUACAGGUGCCCACCACCAUGCCUGGCUUAAUUUUUUGUAUUUUUAGUAGAGAUGAGGUUUCACCAUGUUGGCCAGACUGGUCUCGAACUCCUGACCUCAAAUGAUCCGCUGUCUUGUCCUCCCAAAGUGCUGGGAUUAUAGGCGUGAGCCAUCGCGCCCUGCUGCAUUUCAUUUUUUUGUAUAAAAUUUGGUUUGUUCGUUUUUGAGGGGAACCAUUCCUUUAUGUUGCCCCUUACUGAUGCCCAACUAAUGUGUUUCUGGUUACUAACAGACCUUCAUCCCCCACCCUCCCUAAAUUCUUCGGUGUAAUCUAAGCGUUAUCUGCACCACUUCUGAAUAAUAAAUGUGUUUGAAAUGCACACCUACACAACCCUGUCCCACACUGGCCUGUAGGACCUAAUCUACCUUCAUGUCUUUCAGUUGAUUUGUAUUUCUGCAAAAGAUAUUUCAAGGAUUAUCAAGGUAUGGAAUUUUUUUUAUUUUUUAUCUUUUAACAAACUUGUUCAUUUCCUUUUCUUUCCAUUGAGCACCUCUGAACAAUGUGAUUCUUUUUUUUAAGUCUUUCACACUUCAGGAAAAUACUACAUUCACCCACGUUGUGAUUCAUAUCGGACAGUUUCUUACUCAAAGAUAACACAAAUACCAAUUCUUAUUCAUACUUUGAAACUAUAUUUUACCCUAGACUGCCUUGGUUCAAAGGCCUAGUUUCGACAUUACUGUGGCAAAUUAUUUAAGCUCUCUGUUUUCAUUUCUUUUUCUGUAAAUGCAGGAUGAAAACAAUAUGUAUCUCCUAGGAUGGCUGUGAGGAGUGAGUGAGACAGGACAUGAAAGGUGUGUAUGAACUGUGAUAACUGUUGCCCUUGUGGGCAUGUUAUAUAGGGCUGGCUCUAGGAAGAAGCCUGUGUCUUUUUUCAGAAAUCCCUGGAGCAACUUAAAUGUCUUUAGAAAUGACAAGUCUCUCAGUUAUCCAGUUAGCCGUAAACAGGUUCUGGAAGACACACCUAGAUAGAACUCGGCCCGUCAGUUCUGAGUGAGGCACGUACCACUUGGGCUUGGGAUGUCCUUAACCCAUUUAUGCCUGAGGUUGCAAUUUUUUGAAUUUUUCCAAUCACACCUUGGCGAUGACCUUGAGCAGUAGGAUAUAAAUAACUCCCACAUGCUUAGUGUUCCAAUAAUGGAACACUAGGCAUAAACAGGUUUUAAUUGGCUCCUCAGUCAACCAUGACCAAUAUCUCUAUCUCAGCUUCUGCUGAUGCCCUAGCUCAGGGCUCUGCAUUCCGUGCCAGGGACGCCUCAGCCCCUUAACAUGGAUGUGCCACAUGACAGGCAAUAAUAUAUUGGCCCCAUUAGCCCUUCCUGGAGCAGUCAUAAUGAAUUACAGUCAUGACAGGCACAUGUAAGAAACCAAAAUUUGCUAAAUAUGUACAUGAGUCUUCAUCACAGCAUCGUUUAUGAAAACAACUAAAUAUUCACUAAUGGUGCCAGUGGAAUAAAUCAGAGAACAUCCCCUGCUACGUAACUCUCUGCAUACAUCAAAGAGAAUGGUGUGGCUUUGCUUUUUCAACAAUCUACUGAGUGGCCAUGGGCAUGUGGAUAUGGCCAUGAAUGAGCAAGAUCCUCUCUGAUCCUGUAGAAGUUAAGUUCUACCAGAUAACUUGCUGCUUCAACAAAAAGAUUUACCUUUUUAAAUAAAUGUUGUAGAAUACUUAAAAAAAACAAACUAGAAUUUGCCUGUGUGCAGCCAGUAACAUGUCUAUUUAACCUGGACACCUUUUGAGGAAUAUUCUCAGAUUGCCCCCAUGCUGUUUAUAAGACAUUGUUCCUUAUACACCUGUUUAUGAAUGAAAAGAAACAUAAGGAGUGGGUACAAAGACUUCUAUCUAUGAAUGAUUAAAAAGGCUAGAGUACGAAUACUUCUUGAACCUUUGGUACUAAAUGCUUUUCAUGUUCUAUAUAAAUGUAGAAAACAUUUUACAAAUCCUGUAAAUAAACUGUUUAUUUUUUAUAGAAAGCCA